CCCGAGCUGUGGAAAAUGCCUGUCCACCCGGCAUGGCUGGGUAGUGCCUGCCUCCCCCACGCCAGCCACGGGCCGGCUCCCCAGUCCUCUGUGGGAGGGUUGCUGGUCUCUGUUAAAAGCCCCCCGGGUGACGUGCAUGCCGCCAGGGCCUGUGCCCCCGGGAGACACUCUGGGGAGGGGCCACCACAAGGAAACCUCAGUCCAAGCUGUCCAGCGGAGGCUGGGCAUGGCUGUGCCAGCACAGGAAGGCAGGUAGGGGUCUCCGGGGCAGGCAGCUCUCCCUCUGGCCCAGCCCCCUGUGUGAAGUGCUCAGCCUGGGUAGGAACGUGCUUCCCACUCAGCCUCCUCCAAGCCGCUGGAGGUCCCGCUGGUUCCCCAAAUGGCUUCUGUCCUGAGCCGUGGGCUCCUGACCACGCACCUACCUUGCACGGUCUGAACAAGAGUCUGUGCCAGGGACCCCGCUCAGGAGGGGCACAGAGGAAGCCAAGGGCCCACACAGGUGAGGGGGUCUCAGGUCUGGGCCUCACCCAGCCCAGGCUCAGCAGCAGCCUCAGAAUUUCCUGGCAUCUGCUUGCCUGUGUUGCAACCCAAGUGGGGUGUGCAUGCCGCCUGAGAGAGAAGACACUCGGGGAGGAUUAUGUAAGCGCUUUCCUCCCCAGCACAGGGCCGUCUUGGGCACAUUGCGACCAGACCAUGUGCAAAAGCACUCGGGAGAGUGGCAGGAGCUGACCCACCAGAGAGGGAUUAACCCCUUCCGGGAUGCUGGCGGCUUGUCCUGGGGAACGUGGGGCUGGUCAGGAUUGCAGGACACGGAGGGGCGGAGUGUGAAUGUGGAGGCACCGGUGCUGCGUGAUUUUCCACAAGUUGUCUAACCUCUCUGUGCCUUCGUUGCCUGACUCGGCUGUUUCCAAUGCAGCUGAUUUUAACAGCACCUGUUUCAUGAGGCCACAGCCAG